AGAUGCUGCAUAACAUGAAAGGACAGUUUGCUGAGCAUCUUCUUGGAGCUGGAUUUGUAAGCAGUAGAAAUCCUAAAGAUCCAGAAUCUAAUAUAAAUUCAGAUAAUGAGAAGAUAAUUAAAGCUGUCAUCUGUGCUGGUUUAUAUCCCAAAGUUGCUAAAAUUCGACUAAAUUUGGGUAAAAAAAGAAAAAUGGUAAAAGUUUACACAAAAACCGAUGGCCUGGUUGCUGUUCAUCCUAAAUCUGUUAAUGUGGAGCAAACAGACUUUCACUACAACUGGCUUAUCUAUCACCUAAAGAUGAGAACAAGCAGUAUAUACUUGUAUGACUGCACAGAGGUUUCCCCAUACUGUCUCUUGUUUUUUGGAGGUGACAUUUCCAUCCAGAAGGAUAACGAUCAGGAAACUAUUGCUGUAGAUGAGUGGAUUGUAUUUCAGUCUCCAGCAAGAAUUGCCCAUCUUGUUAAGGAAUUAAGAAAGGAACUAGAUAUUCUUCUGCAAGAGAAGAUUGAAAGUCCUCAUCCUGUAGACUGGAAUGACACUAAAUCCAGAGACUGUGCAGUACUGUCAGCUAUUAUAGACUUGAUCAAAACACAGGAAAAGGCAACUCCCAGGAACUUUCCGCCACGAUUCCAGGAUGGAUAUUACAGCUGACAGCUUUUCAGGGGUGGUCUGAAAAGCCAGUUUGACAGCCAUUCUUCAUCAUUGUUUAAAUUUUGGCUGGAUGCCAAACCCUGGGACAUGAACAAUUUUCAUGUGUAAGGUAGAAGCCUUCAGUAGGUAGUAAAGACUUAAUGUGCAUGACUUGAUGUUAUAUGUAGAGAUAUAUAUAUAUAUAUAUAUAUACCAUAAAAGCAAUAUGUUCUCUGAUCAUAUACUCUGCUGUGGUCAUGCCCACUCUUUGGGAGUAUAUUCCCUUUAUAUAUAUUGAGUAUUGUACCACUUGAGAAAUUCCUUUGUUCUGUUAUACAAAAUUAAUCUUUCUGCUCAUAAUGAUUGAUGAUACCACCAGUAAAAAUAGGAUGUUUACCCCAAAACAAGUGUCAAUUAAGAAUUUGAACACAACCACAUUUUUUAAAAUGAAACUUCUAUCGGAAGUAAAUUAAUUUGUUGUAAUAAAGUCCAGUAUUUAAUAAAAUGUACAAUGUUAAAUCUCAGCCAACCUCUUGGAUUGGUUUCUACAUUUUCACCUAUGGCUUGGUUCAUUUGAUAUUUUUACUAUUUUUAAAACACGUGCCCUUUUUAUAUCACCCUGUGCCUCAUAAUACAGCAAUUGAGAGCACGGUCUGGAGCCUGAUUACCUCAGUUCCAGUCUCAGCUCUGUCAGUUAGUCAGUGUCUUGGCUUCUCUCCUUUUUCCUUAUCUUGUAAGAUACAGUUGGCCCUUCAUAUCCAUGCAUUCCACAUCUGUGGAUUCAAACAACUGUGGAUAGAAGAUAUUUGGGGAAAAAAAGGAUGGUUGUGUCUAUACUGAACAUGUGCAGACUUUUUUCCUUGUCAUUCCCUAAACAAUACAGUUUAACAGCUAUUUAUAUAGUAUUUACAUUGUAUUAGGUAUUAUAAAUAAUCUAGAGAUGACUUAAAGAAUAUGGGAGGUUGUGCCUAGGUAACAUGCAAAUACUACGCCAUUUUAUUAUAAAAGACUUGAGCAUCCAUGGAUUUAGGUAUUUGAGGGGUUGGGGUUGGAAACCAGUCCCCCACAGAUACUGAGGGACAACUGUACAUGUAACAGUUGUGAGGAUGAAGUACAUUAAUACAUGUAAAGCACAUAGGCUAGUGCCUGUACUCUCUGAAUCUUAGUUGUUAUUUGUCCCUGAAAUAUUUUCGUAAAUGUCUAACAAUCUAUUAUAUUACACUUUUUAUUUUAUUGCUACUUAUCUUCUUCGCCAAGGAAUAGUGUAACAACACAUGCUGUACAUUUUCAGCCCUAUCAGAUUGUGAUAAAUACUGUUGGUUGCCGGCCAGCAACUAUUUUGUCCCUCCCUUCUUGCUUGCUUAUUCUGGUGUUCCCUUCUGUGCAGCUCUGUGUCCAGGUAUGUUGGACCCUUUCCCUAAGGGUGAAUCCUGCUGUUCUAAAUGAAUCACAUGUGGUCUUAUCCCCCUUAUAAGUAAUUGAUAAGGCAUGAGUACAUAAACAUGUCCUAGUGAAUGGCAGCUGAGAAGUGAUCUUCAAGGGGGUGUCUGAAAAAUGUUUUACUCACUAAUAGGCUUAGAGGAGGAAAUCCUGCUCUCUCUGGACAUUGUCUUUUCUGACUCUGAUAGUUGGAACUGCUGCAGCCAACUAAUGAUCACAAGGAGACACGGACUCAGACUGAGGUUAGCUCAGUGGAAAGAUAGAACUCACCAGAGCCUUUGAUAAUGCCGGUAAGCUUCAGAAUUAACCCAUUCUAGAGCUGCUUUACAUGUGGACUUAUGUUGAUAUAAUAAAAACCCUUCAAUUGUUUAAGCCACUUUUAAUAGGAUAUUGUUAGUUUUUUGUUGGUUUUUUGUUUUGUUUUGUUUUGUUUUUUGUUUUUUGGAGACAGUGUCUUGCCCUGUCACCCAGGCUGGAGUGCAGUGGUGUGAUCUUGGUUCACUGCAGCCUCGACUUCCUGGGUUCAAGUGAUCCUUCUGCCUCAGCCUCCCAAAUAGCUGGGACUAUAGGCAUGCAUCACCACACCCAGCUAAUUUCUGUAUUUUUUGUAGAGACACCGUUUCACCAUGUUGCCCAGGCUGGUCUCAAAACUCCUGUGCUCAAGCAGUCUGCCCGCCUUGGCUUCCCAAAGUGCUGACAUUACAGGUAUGAGCCACUGCACCCGGUCCCUAGUAGGGUAUUUUUAACUUGGCAAAAAGGGUAUUAAUCAGAAACAUACACUAUCCAUCACUGAGUAUUAUACUCUUGAUUUUGCAAUGUAAGAGUUUUAACCUAUUUGUCUGACAGAAGGUGUAAAAGUGCUGGACAUGCUGCAGAAAGAAACAGGAAAAGCAUCUUGCUGCACUCCAAAGAAUGCAAAUUUUAAUGUGCCUUCCAAUAAAUGCAAGGAAACCGAAAGAGUUAAUAGUAUCAUACAAUGACUGGGAUGUAUUGAUAAUGCUACAGUGAUCCAUUAACAGCACUUGUUCAGGUACUGCUCCCAAUCCUGGGAAUGUGUGUUACCUGUUAUGUCUCAAAUCCUUUAUCUUGGCUGUUCUUCUAAAAGUGAUCUGUCUGUCAUUGAAUGCUGGCAUUAGAGUCAUGUCACAAUAUUAGAGCAUACUGGUUUUGCCUCUAACGUCGAGGUGACCAUCUGGUCUUUCUUGCUCUGUAAGAGUUUCUGUUUGUGCUUUUUUUUCCCUUACUUUUAUUAUCCAGUUUAAAUCCAGUCAGUUGGCCAAAAUGGUCUUGGAAGAAAGGAUUUAGAGAUUCUGUAAAAAAGAUUAUUAGUUGGUUCUGUGUUUGCAAACCAGUAUGUAAUUCCCAUAUGAAUGGGGAAAAUGUUCCUGAGGAAUUAUUUAAUUGAUGAGGCAUUCACAGAGAUUAAAGCAGUUAUUGUUACCUCCAAUUUAUGUCUUCUGCACAGCUGAUUAGGUUGGACAUUUUAAUCCAAGGUGCUACUUACAUUCUGUUUCUUUUGUUUACAAAAUAGGGCAUUACUGAGUAGAAAAUACAUUCCAGGUCUAAGAACUGUUUGUUCUUUAGUGGAUUUUAAAGAAUAAGACAUUAAAUUAAGAAGGAAAAUCUGUUUGAUUCAUCAUUUUGAGUAAUGCAGAGAAUAACUCUUAAAAAAAAAACCUGAAACAGAAACUUUCAGGAAAAAAACAAAAGAAAUUAAACUACUGAAUAAUCUUUCAAAAGCAUCGUUGAACAGUGAGCACAUGUGAUGCCUUCCCAAUUAAUUAAUUUGGGCAAAAGCUCUAGAUAAACUUACACCAAUUGUUGCAAGGCAUUCUCUAUUACUGCAUUUUUAAAACAAAGUCCUCCCCUAAAAGUUAUGAAUUAUACAAAAGCUUUAGGAGGAAUUUUAGUACUCCUUUACCCAAAAUAAAUAGUGGUAAAUUUCCUUCUGUUCUUAGCUCUGAGUUUGUAUUUAUUUAUAAGUCAUUGUGAUCAUGUAUACUUAUAUAUUUUUAAUAUGCUAAUUGCUUUUAAAUGGGAUUUUUGUUCUGAUUUUAAAAUAAUACAUCCUCCCUGGACAAUAUUUGGAAAUGUAGCAAAGUAAAUCAUGUUACCAUUGUUCCAUUUUGAUAUAUAUAAACUUUAGGUAUUAUUUUAUAUAUAAUAAAUUUUAAGAUAUUAUAUACAAUAAAAUUAACCAAUUUAA